AAUCUAGGCUGCCUGAGGAUGAUUGGAGGGUAUCGUAGGACGGUUAGAAGGAGGCUCAAGAUGUAUAUAUGUGUUUUUCUGUUAGUGUUUGAGAAUAGUUUCAGAUAGCCACAAUGGAUAUUCAUUUGGCGUGUGAGUAGGAGUUGAGUGAAUUUCCAUGUUAAAAACUUGUGAGUGUUGGGGCGGAGAAUUUCAGCAUUUUCUAGAAAUCUGGAUUUAGAAUUUAUCAGUAACUUCUGCCUCAUAAGGAAAAGGAGAGGCAUUCCGCUUGGGAAUUUUAUAUAAAUGUUUUAUUUUUUCUUAAUCAUUAGAUAGUUUACAGUUAUGUGCUUUUUGCUGCCCUGUAGAUGCGUGACAACCCUUCUGUCCCAUCAUUGGGGUUGAAAUGAGGACAGCACCGAAGAGUGCAGUUUCUGGUCGAUGAAUACUGCUUCUAAGAUCUUUGUGGAAGAUAUUAAUCAAAUGCAGUUAAAAAGUAUACGUAUAAUAUGUAUAUUAUAUAUAUAUAUACACACACACACGUAAUAGCCUGUAGUGAGAUUAUUUUAAAGACACUUCCUAGUGUUAAAGAACCCUUGAAGUGUUUCGAGUUCUUAUUGUUUUGGUAAUGCUAAAAGCUUGGGGUUGUGUGAAUGGGGGUGGGGGGUGUGGUGUGAUGUAUUCUAAUGACUUGAGUUAUUCUGGGUGCUAGGAAUAAGAGUUAUUAUAUUUACCAGGAUUACUAUGCUGAAGGUAUUCUUCAAGAGUUUGUUUUUUUUCUACUGGUUGAUCUCUACUUUUAGAAGUCAUUGAAAUUAUGAGACUAUCAUUCAAAUGGAAGCAUUAUAGUUCUUCGGAACCAUUAUGAUCUCAAAACGAAAGGAGAAUGAUACAGAUACACUGGCUGAGGUGUUUUGAGGUGCAUCGAAGUGUUCCAAGCUGUGACUUACCUUAACAUGUUCUUGAAGUACCAUGGCGUGGAUUAAAAGGAAAUUUGGUGAGCGGCCUCCACCUAAACGACUUACUAGGGAAGCUAUGCGAAAUUAUUUAAAAGAGCGAGGGGAUCAAACAGUACUUAUUCUUCAUGCAAAAGUUGCACAGAAGUCAUAUGGAAAUGAAAAAAGGUUUUUUUGCCCACCUCCUUGUGUAUAUCUUAUGGGCAGUGGAUGGAAGAAAAAAAAAGAACAAAUGGAACGCGAUGGUUGUUCUGAACAAGAGUCUCAACCGUGUGCAUUUAUUGGGAUAGGAAAUAGUGACCAAGAAAUGCAGCAGCUAAACUUGGAAGGAAAGAACUAUUGCACAGCCAAAACAUUGUAUAUAUCUGACUCAGACAAGCGAAAGCACUUCAUGUUGUCUGUAAAGAUGUUCUAUGGCAACAGUGAUGACAUUGGUGUGUUCCUCAGCAAGCGGAUAAAAGUCAUCUCCAAACCUUCCAAAAAGAAGCAGUCAUUGAAAAAUGCUGACUUAUGCAUUGCCUCAGGAACAAAGGUGGCUCUGUUUAAUCGACUACGAUCCCAGACAGUUAGUACCAGAUACUUGCAUGUAGAAGGAGGUAAUUUUCAUGCCAGUUCACAGCAGUGGGGAGCCUUUUUUAUUCAUCUCUUGGAUGAUGAUGAAUCAGAAGGAGAAGAAUUCACAGUCCGAGAUGGCUACAUCCAUUAUGGACAAACAGUCAAACUUGUGUGCUCAGUUACUGGCAUGGCACUCCCAAGAUUGAUAAUUAGGAAAGUUGAUAAGCAGACCGCAUUAUUGGAUGCAGAUGAUCCUGUGUCACAACUCCAUAAAUGUGCAUUUUACCUUAAGGAUACAGAAAGAAUGUAUUUGUGCCUUUCUCAAGAAAGAAUAAUUCAAUUUCAGGCCACUCCAUGUCCAAAAGAACCAAAUAAAGAGAUGAUAAAUGAUGGCGCUUCCUGGACAAUCAUUAGCACAGAUAAGGCAGAGUAUACAUUUUAUGAGGGAAUGGGCCCUGUCCUUGCCCCAGUCACUCCUGUGCCUGUGGUAGAGAGCCUUCAGUUGAAUGGCGGUGGGGACGUAGCAAUGCUUGAACUUACAGGACAGAAUUUCACUCCAAAUUUACGAGUGUGGUUUGGGGAUGUAGAAGCUGAAACUAUGUACAGGUGUGGAGAGAGUAUGCUCUGUGUCGUCCCAGACAUUUCUGCAUUCCGAGAAGGUUGGAGAUGGGUCCGGCAACCAGUCCAGGUUCCAGUAACUUUGGUCCGAAAUGAUGGAAUCAUUUAUUCCACCAGCCUUACCUUUACCUACACACCAGAACCAGGGCCGCGGCCACAUUGCAGUGCAGCAGGAGCAAUCCUUCGAGCCAAUUCAAGCCAGGUGCCCCCUAACGAAUCAAACACAAACAGCGAGGGAAGUUACACAAACGCCAGCACAAAUUCAACCAGUGUCACAUCAUCUACAGCCACAGUGGUAUCCUAACUACCGUCUUUUUGCUAGGACUUAAACUGACUUGAGUGUGGCAAAAAGUUAACAAAAAAGGAGAAAAAAUGAACAAUCGUUUGUGGUUUCUUGGGAAAACUUUUCAUACCAGGUGAUACUAUUCAAAAACCCCGUUGUCUCCCUGCAAGUGCUGAUUUGAAAUGCAGAAGCCACAGUAAAAAAAAAAAAAAAAAAAAAAAAAAAGAAAAAAAAAUCAAAAUGUAUAAAUAUUGGAAAUCAAGUUUUUCAGCUGUUUUGUUGGUUGGUUGGUUGGUUUUUGUUUGGUUUUGUUUAAAUGGGCAAGAAGUAAAUAAUGUGGCUGGAAUACAAGUUGAACAAACUAGAAGACACAAAUCUAACAUAGUUUUUAUGGACCAAGGAACUUGUAUAUUGUAUAAGCUUUAGUAAAAGGUACAUUUUCACCAUACCUUUUUUUAUAUCACGGUAUUAUAGUACACCUUGUUACCAAAUAGGUUGUUCUCUUCCCCACCCACCUUUGAGCUUUUGCUCUAAAAUACAUUCAGGUUCCAAGCCUGACCAUCCUUGUUUAAUCUAUCAUACUCUUCCAGGUUUUUUUUUUUUGGUCUAAGGCUGGAACUUUUUUCUUUUUUUUCAGCUGAAGUCUUAUGACUUUUCAUGAGUCAAAAUUGUUUGGAUUUCAGCAAGUCAAAUCUUGCAAAGGCCUGCAUAUUUUUUUUAAGAUUAUAUGAAGUCUGUGCAAAAGCUUUAAAAAAAUGCCUCUGCCUUGCCUGCAAUACAUGCAAUGUAUGUUAACUUAGUCUCUCUUCUCAGACACUGUUGGUAGUUAUUUCUGUGUUUUCCUUUUUUUAAAAAAAAAUAUGGACUUAUUGUGGUUAUCUGAGAGGUUCUAACAUUCACAUGCAAUUUGGUGUGGCCAUUUAGCUAUUAAUGAGUUAAUGGCGCAGAACUUGUUGAUAUUUGAAGUGUUCUCUCCCCUUUUCCCAUGACGUAAAUACAUAGGUGUGUUCCAGGAUUUGUUCAGGUUUUUCCCCCCUCCUAAUCUUGUACAUAACUUGUAUUAUGUGUAAGUUAAACAUUUUAUUUUGAACUUGGAAUGUUCCCAGUGAUUUCAUUCAGCAGGGUAUUUUCUGCCUUGUUGGCAAGUGACAAAAAAUAUGGGAAGUAUUUGCUACCAGUUGGUAGAUGGUGCCCUUAAUGGUAGAAUGAGGAAAAUGUCCGCAAAAGCAUGUUUUAUUAUCUUUACUUUUUUGGGGGGUUGGAGGGGGUAGCCUAGCCAGAACAUCAUUGUAAUCUUAAAACAUAAGAUGCUUUUAUUAGAUGAUCAACUAAAAUAGCUGGAAGACAGUACUUUAGAAACAGAUAGUUGUAAGAUUAUAAAAUGCAAAUGUAACUUAUGUUUUCAUUUUUUUCUCUGCCUUUUUUGUUUGUUUGUUUUCUCUUUUCCAGUACUGAGCAUCUCCACAAAUGUCUCCUAACUCAGAAAAUGUUUCUUUUCUUUUCAGUUGAGAUUUGGUUGCAUUCAGGGUUGUAGGUUGGCCUUGCUUGCUAACCCCGCCGGUUUUACCGUGCUUUCAUUCCUGAACUUUGUUUAUGCCUUUGUUUGGUUUCUUCGAAAUUGCAGCAGACUCAUUGGGCUACAUUUAGUACAGGAACCACGUGUGUAAUGUUAUACAACACAGUCUAGUAAUACAAUCAUCCCUCUUAGAGUAAAAACUACCUCUAGAUUGUGGUAAGCUUUUACUGUCCCAUAAAACAGGAGCCACAGUACCUUAUGAAUGCAAAACUGUAACUUCCUACAGUGUUUCCCUACAGAACAUUGUCUUUCUGGUGUCCUGGGCUGUUUUGAAAAAGUUUCCAUUAAUAGACUUUUUAGAAAUUAUUAUUAGUAGCAUUUUUUUUCCAGCUUUGCUGUCUUCAUCACUCACUCUAUGCUCAGACUAUGCCACUGUAAAUAUUCUUCCUAACAUCUUUAAAUCGCCUUUUCCUCAGUUUUCAAGGGGAAGGUCAUUUGUAAAGCACGUUAGGUGGUUAAAUCAGUUAUUGCGGUUUUCUCUUACUGCAAGCCUUUUUAAUCACCCCCAGGCUGCAUUUUAUUCUAUAUCGCCUUUUUUCUUCAAAUCUGCUCCAAUCACUCACUUCUCUCUUAUAAGCUAAUCCUGCCUCACACCUUAAAUCUGUUUCAGUGAUCAAGGGCAGAACUCAUUGUGGCCUUAUCUUUCUUUGUUGUAAUUGUUCACUGUCUCUUUCUUACAGACCACUUAUUUCUGAGUAGUAGUUAUUCCUCUCUAUGGAGUCAUGGCAGGAAUCAUUACACAGUGCUUUUGUUCAGAGCAUGGACAUGUUCCUAGUGCUGCUUUGCUUUAACGGCCACAAGUUUCCUCCACUUCCUAGGUUUGGUAUUUAGUUAAGGAAUCAUAUUAAAUUAACCAAUAACAAAAGAGAUACUUUUGAAGAACAAACUAUUCCUUACCCAUUUUUGUAGCUCAAAAAUAAUUUUUCAAGUUCAUGACCUUAUUAAAAUGAACUUGUGUUUUUUUAACAAACAUGUAUGUUUUAUUUUGAUAGUUUCUUUCCGUAAGAUAAUUGAAAUAUUAUACUGUAAACCCUUUUCUUUUCUUUUUUUGAAAAGUCCAAGAAUGUACUUAUACAGGCAUUUUUCCCCACCUAUUUUUGGCCAUUCUCAUACCACAGACUAAAGAGUGAAAUGAUUUGUCCAUUGUAGCUUAUUGUUUAUCAGUAGUUCUUUUGUCAGCUGCUUACAUUUUUUCUUUCAUGGUUUUGUGAAUCAUUUUCAGUAUGUAAUUUAUAGGAACCUUGUCCUCUGGUUAUAGUAGACUGUGUGCCCUCCUCCAGUGAUGGCAUUAUUAGACAUGCUGGUCAUUUACCCUCAGAAAGACUCUCUUAUUAGAAUGGUGAGUGCUUCAGUUAUAGUAUGUUUGAAUUUUUAAAAAAUUCUGUUUUAGAAAUGUAUCUUAUGCUCUCAUGACUAUGCAGUUUCUAAACAUACACAUAGAAGCUGAGUCUCUGAUCCAAUAUGUUUUUAUUUGUUCCAUUUAAUUUAUCACAUAGAUUGGGAAGGCAAGCUAAAAGCCUUAAAAAUGCCCUUUAUAUUUUGAGUGAUUUCAGCGUUGAACACUAGUAUACUAUCUAAAUUUGCUGCUCACUUUCUUUAAACUGUGGCAAUUAAAGGCAUGUUUAUACAUGACUUAAUCGUGAAAUGUUUGUCACUCUUACUGCACAGACUUAUCUGCAAUCAUAACUGGUUAGUUUUUUUGUUUUGUUUUGUUUUAUUGUUUUUAAUGAAACUGGUACCAUCUGUGCUUUCACAAAAAACUUCCAAUGCCAUUUUUGAGAACUAACCUAACUAGUCAUGCUAACCAGAAAAUCCACUGGGGAGGAGGUUCCUUUUGAAACAAAAUGCUGUUCAGUUAGUAACCAAGUUACUUUGAUUGCAAAAGCAGCUGUGUUUCUGAUAAGUACUGAACAAAUGUGUGUAAUUUUCUGUGCCAGACUUAUGACUUUGUUUUCAAGCACUGUAAUGUGGGAUGGAUGGUUAGAAACAAUAAUAUAUUAGGGUUUCUGUUUAACCCUUUCAGGACUGAACUGUAUCUCCUUUUGUUAAUUUUCCCCUGUGUUGUGAUAAAUGUUUGCCAGCAUUCAGUACUGUGUUGGUCCAGAUGUAGGUUUAUAUGCUCAUUUUUAGCUUAUUUCUUGUACCUUGCAGCAUGCUCUACGCAUUCAGUCCUUAAGGGGUUUAUUUUACAAACUGUGCGCCUGUAAGGUUUAUUAGCAAUAAGAUAGAAAAUUGAGCAAGUUUAUACCAUAAUUUUGUAGAAAAAAAGAAUCUGCUCAGUUCCAUAUUUCAUCCGUGAAAAACUUGCAAUACGAGCAGUUUCAAGGAAUAAAUAAAAAGGAAAUGUAAACCAUUGUAAAAGUCUUCUGUCGAAUGUGCCUGAUGCAUGUAUUAUCGUCUUUUAUUUCAGAAUACUUCAUAAAGAUAAAAUUAAAUUCUAUAUUAUAGUUGGUGUAUUUACAAUCUUACCAUGUACAUCACAUCAAAGUGAUAGCUCUACUAAUUUAAUUUCCUUGUCAAUGUUUUUAACUAUAUAGUGCUUUAAAGAGAUUUUUUUUCCCUGUGUAAA